GCGCACUCGGCUCGGCCCGGCCCGGGCCGCAGCAUGGCCGAGCCGCUACUCAGGAAAACCUUCUCCCGCCUGCGGGGCCGGGAGAAACUUCCCCGGAAAAAGUCGGACGCCAAGGAGCGCGGCCACCCAGCCCAGCGCCCAGAGCCCAGCCCUCCAGAGCCAGAGCCCCAGGCUCCCGAAGGGUCCCAGGCCGGAGCAGAGGGGCCCUCCAGCCCCGAGGCAUCAAGGAGCCCUGCACGGGGAGCCUACCUGCAAAGCCUGGAGCCCAGUAGCCGCCGAUGGGUGCUGGGUGGGGCCAAGCCAGCUGAGGACACCUCUUUAGGGCCUGGGGUACCUGGCACUGGGGAGCCCGCCGGCGAGAUCUGGUACAACCCCAUCCCUGAGGAAGACCCCAGACCUCCAGCACCUGAGCCCCCGGGGCCACAGCCUGGCUCAGCUGAGUCAGAGGGCCUGGCCCCCCAAGGUAAGAACAAGCUUCCCAUCCCCUUCCCCAAGGUGAGCACCAGCUCCACAUCCCUUCCCUUCAGGGUAGCACCAGCCUCACACUCCCUCCUCCCAGAGGAGCACCAACCUCACACUCCUUCCCUUCAGGGGAGCACCAGCCUCACAUCCCCACCCCGUCAGAUGCUCCCAGAGGAGCAUCAGCCUCACACCCUCCUCCCCGCCAGGGGAACACCAGCCUCACACUCCUUCCCUUCAGGGGAGCACCAGCCUCACCCCCCUCCCCUAAGCCCAGGUUCCUGGACCCUGAAGUCUGCUCUCCACACAGGUGCAGCCCCCGCCAGCCCCCCAACCAAAGCCUCCCGCACCAAGUCCCCGGGCCCCGCCAGGCGCCUCUCCAUAAAGAUGAAGAAGCUGCCGGAACUGCGGCGCCGCCUGAGCCUGCGAGGCCCCCGGGCUGGCAGGGAGCGCGAGAGGGCUGCCCCUGCGGGCUCCGUCAUCAGCCGCUACCACCUGGACAGCAGCGUGGGGGGCCCCGGGCCGGCAGCAGGGCCUGGGGGCACCCGGAGCCCGAGGGCCGGUUACCUCAGCGACGGGGACUCACCGGAGCGCCCAGCUGGGCCCCCAUCACCCACCUCCUUCCGGCCCUACGAGGUGGGUCCCGCAGCCCGGGCACCCCCGGCCGCACUCUGGGGCCGCCUCAGCCUGCACCUGUACGGUCUCGGGGGGCUGCGGCCAGCGCCGGGGGCCACCCCCAGGGACCUCUGCUGCCUACUGCAAGUGGAUGGGGAGGCCAGGGCCCGAACAGGGCCACUGCGAGGGGGGCCGGACUUCCUGCGGCUGGACCACACCUUCCACCUGGAGCUGGAGGCCGCCAGGCUCCUGCGCGCCCUGGUGCUUGCGUGGGACCCUGGCGUGAGAAGGCACCGGCCCUGUGCCCAGGGCACCGUGCUGCUGCCCACGGUCUUCCGAGGGUGCCAGGCCCAACAGCUGGCCGUGCGCCUGGAGCCUCAGGGGCUGCUGUAUGCCAAGCUGACCCUGUCGGAGCAGCAGGAAGCCCCUGCCACAGCUGAGCCCCGCGUCUUUGGGCUGCCCCUGCCACUGCUGGUGGAGCGGGAGCGGCCCCCCGGCCAGGUGCCCCUCAUCAUCCAGAAGUGCGUUGGGCAGAUCGAGCGCCGAGGGCUGCGGGUAGUGGGACUGUACCGUCUUUGUGGCUCAGCGGCAGUGAAGAAAGAGCUUCGGGAUGCCUUUGAGCGGGACAGUGCAGCGGUCUGCCUAUCUGAGGACCUGUACCCCGAUAUCAAUGUCAUCACUGGCAUCCUCAAGGAUUAUCUUCGAGAGUUGCCCACCCCACUCAUCACCCAGCCCCUGUAUAAGGUGGUACUGGAGGCCAUGGCCCGGGACCCCCCAAACAGAGUUCCCCCCACCACUGAGGGCACCCGAGGGCUCCUCAGCUGCCUGCCAGAUGUGGAAAGGGCCACGCUGACGCUUCUCCUGGACCACCUGCGCCUCGUCUCCUCCUUCCAUGCCUACAACCGCAUGACCCCACAGAACUUGGCCGUGUGCUUCGGGCCUGUGCUGCUGCCGGCACGCCAGGCGCCCACAAGGCCUCGUGCCCGCAGCUCCGGCCCAGGCCUUGCCAGUGCAGUGGACUUCAAGCACCACAUCGAGGUGCUGCACUACCUGCUGCAGUCUUGGCCAGAUCCCCGCCUGCCCCGACAAUCUCCAGAUGUCGCGCCUUACUUGCGACCCAAACGACAGCCACCUCUGCACCUGCCGCUGGCAGACCCCGAAGUGGUGACUCGGCCCCGCGGUCGAGGAGGCCCCGAAAGCCCCCCGAGCAACCGCUACGCCGGCGACUGGAGCGUUUGCGGGCGGGACUUCCUGCCCUGUGGGCGGGAUUUCCUGUCCGGGCCAGACUACGACCACGUGACGGGCAGUGACAGCGAGGACGAGGACGAGGAGGUCGGCGAGCCGAGGGUCACCGGUGACUUCGAAGACGACUUCGAUGCGCCCUUCAACCCGCACCUGAAUCUCAAAGACUUCGACGCCCUCAUCCUGGAUCUGGAGAGAGAGCUCUCCAAGCAAAUCAACGUGUGCCUCUGAGCCAGAUGACGGGGUGGGACCCCGGUUAGUAAGGACCGGGCGCCCAGUGGCUAAGGCGGUGCCCUGGUGACCAAGGAGAGCCAGACCUGUUGCUCAGGCCGAGCUCCUGGUUGCCAGCGAGUUACCACGGGACCAGUCGCGUGUAUGGCUGAGACUCAUUCCCAGUUUCCAGGGCCCGGUAUUUGGACACUAGUUGCCAAGUCUGGGGCCUGGGGAUUUUAGGGACCAGCGGUUGUGACCAUCUUUCCUGAGCACCAAGGGCUUCCCCUUUUGUUGCCAAAAAGGUAGUUCUCGCGCUUGCUAGGCUGGCCUCUCUUGCCUCCCCUUGGCCGGGGCAACACCAGUUACUGUGAGCAUCACCCUGGUGUGGUGAGUCACCUCUAGUCGGCCCUCUUGCUGCUGCCAACCAAAUCAGUAUUAGCUUUGAGCACUGCACUGUUUCUCCCUCCCUUGGACGACACAAAGACUAGCAUGAGGCACUGUUUGUGGGGGGCAGCCCCUAUCCUGGGUUCCAGCAUGGACACAGGGGUAGCCUGGGGCUUAUAGAGAAACAGCUGGUUUCCCCUACCCUUUUCCGGGGAAGUCCCCACGAUUGGCCUCUAGUCAGCAAAUGGAGAUAACAGAGUCUGGCCUUUCCAAUCCCCAUCUCCUUGCCCCCCCCUUGCCCCCCCCCCCGAAAAAAAUUGAGCACUUAAACCCCUCCCUUUUGGAGGGGGCCCCCUGAAGCGUCAGGCUGGGGGCAGUCUGGUACGGAACAUAUUUAUUGCCUCCAUGCAUGUGUGUGUGUGUCUGUGAGGACUGGUGUGCGUGGACACGUCUGAAGCAGGCGUGUGGGGCUCUUUCAGGGACCACAGAGGAGGGAGCAGUUUGCAGUGCCCAGCCACCCUGAAAUCCCCAAUAAUGGUGCCUCAGUGGGCCCCAGAGUUCCAGUGGGAGAGUACGGUUCCCUCCUGUCUCCCUCUUCUUUUCCGCACCUCCAUCUUUGUGGAUAAUAAAUAAAUAUGCACAGGU